GGAGGAUGCGGCGGUCCGACUCGGGUUCUGUUGGGACAGCUCCUCUGCGCCCCGUAGGUCCCUCGGUCAGCGCCUUCCCUUGGGCGCGGCGACCCGGCGCGGGUUUCCAGGGGACAGCUGCCCGGCGCCCCUGAGGUCCCUCGACAGGCACGGCGACCCGGGCACCUGCUGCCGCGACCCUGAUCCUCCGCCGUCGUCGGGCAGGUUGCGGUCCCCGCGGUUCCCUGCAUCUGUUAAGAGGGCGGGGGCCGGGAAGGCGGUGUCCGGGGACGGUGCCCUUGUCCUCGAGGCGGCCCUGGACGCGUCGCCUGCGGGGCCUGAACCGAGGACCCCCCCGUACCCCGCUUUGUCCUGGUGAGGCGCUCCUGCCGCGCAGCGGCAUCUUCCUCUGUUAACGUCGAGAAUGAGUAGUGAAGGCUGCUCAUUAUCCUGCAUUGUAAAGUAAAACUUGUCUUUUUAGAAGCGUCUCCUGAAAAUUGGCGCAUCUCCUGUGCUUCUCUGGGUUGUAUUGGGAAACUGGGCCAGUCGCUGUCAGGACUGUCCUGUUGGCUACAUUAUCCAGGCAGCAGAGGGCAUAAAAGCUGCUUUCCAAAUUUAGAUGGCAAUUUUAGAUGUGAUGCCUGAUGUCAACUAUUCUCAAGUAUGCUAAAGCCCAUUUCUGCUGACCAAGCACCUGAGCAAGUGACCGGGCAGCCUCCACAGGGUCAUCUUUCUGAAGUGUAAAAAGUGGAUAGUGGCUCACGUGUCAAAGGAUGGCACGGUCACGAUCUAGAUCCCCCAGGUGGAAACACAGGUCUUUAUCACCAGUACCUAGAAAUGCUGAACACUACAAGCAAAGACAUUCACACGGGCAUUAUGGCUGUGAAUAUAGGAAGGAUCCAAAAAGACCCGUCGCGUGGAGAAUGGACAGUGAGAAACAUGGACAGAGUAAACCAAGGAUUCCCUCUCGUGGAAAUAUAUAUUACCAGUCUUAUGAACAUAGAUCACCUUCCCCUAACAUAAGAAACUCUUUAGAAAAUGUUUAUAUGUAUAAGCCUCACAGAGGAUAUUCGCCUGGAAGAGGGGACAGUAACAGGAGAGCUCAGUAUAUGCCCAAAUACUCAGAGGGUAUACCCUACAAAGAGCAUGAAAGGAAUUCUUAUCCCCAGAAAGUGCAAGGAGGGCAUAGUCCUGAUGACCACAGAGUUAGAGGAAGUGGAAAAGGAGGGAAACCACCUCAGAGGUCAAUAGCAGAUUCUUUUAGAUUUGAAGGAAAGUGGCAUGAAGAUGAGUUGAGGCACCAGAGGAUACAAGAAGAAAAAUACUCCCAGUCAACUAGAAGAGGCUCUGAAGACUUUGAGACAAGGAGCUCAUUUCAGAAGAGGUAUCCUGAGGAUCGUGAUUUCAGAAAAUAUGGACACACAUCAAAAAGACCUAAAGACGUGGAGAGGUAUGAAAGCAGAGAGCCUGCCAGGAACCCAAAGUGGAAGCCUGAGCAUUCCCUCCCACCUUACCAAGAGGACACAGACCAGUGGAACCUUGGGCCCCAAACUUAUCGACAUGCUGAGAGGGAACACCCAGAGACCAGUUCAGCAACCAAAGUAUCCUAUGACUAUCGUCACAAACGUCCUAAGCUCUUGGAUGGGGACCAGGACUUUUCUGAUGGGAGAACUCAGAAGUACUGUAAGGAAGAAGAUAGAAAAUAUAGUUUUCAAAAAGGCCCUCUAAAUAGAGAGUUAGAUUGUUUUAAUACUGGAAGAGGGAGAGAGACUCAAGAUGGACAAGUCAAAGAACCUUUUAAACCGUCUAAGAAAGACAGCAUUGCCUGUACUUAUUCAAAUAAAAAUGAUGUUGAUUUGCGAUCUAGUAAUGACAAAUGGAAGGAAAAAAUAAAGAAAGAAGGGGAUUGUAGAAAAGAGAGCAAUUCUUCCAGUAACCAACUUGAUAAAAGUCAAAAACUUCCUGAUGUGAAACCCUCGCCUAUCAAUCUUAGGAAGAAAUCACUUACAGUUAAAGUAGAUGUGAAGAAAACAGUAGAUACAUUCAGGGUUGCUUCUAGCUAUUCCACAGAGAGACAGAUGUCACAUGAUUUGGUUGCUGUUGGCAGGAAAAGUGAGAACUUUCAUCCAGUGUUUGAACAUCUUGACUCAACUCAGAAUACUGAAAACAAACCUACAGGAGAAUUUGCUCAGGAAAUCAUAACAAUAAUCCAUCAAGUUAAAGCAAAUUAUUUUCCAUCACCUGGCAUUACUUUACAUGAGCGUUUCUCAACAAUGCAAGAUAUACACAAGGCAGAUGUAAAUGAAAUUCCAUUGAAUUCAGAUCCAGAAAUACACAGGAGAAUAGAUAUGUCUUUGGCCGAGCUUCAGAGUAAACAAGCUGUGAUCUAUGAAUCGGAACAGACUCUGAUCAAAAUAAUAGAUCCAAAUGACCUACGACAUGACAUUGAAAGAAGGCGAAAAGAACGGUUACAGAAUGAAGAUGAGCACAUUUUUCACAUAGCUAGUGCUGCAGAGAGGGAUGAUCAGAAUUCCAGUUUUUCAAAGAAUUAUACUACGCAGAGAAAAGACAUAAUUACUCACAAACCAUUUGAGGUUGAGGGAAACCACCGAAACACAAGAGUAAGACCUUUUAAGAGCAACUUUAGAGGUGGCAGAUGCCAGCCCAAUUAUAAAUCAGGCCUGGUACAGAAGAGCUUGUACAUUCAGGCUAAGUAUCAGCGUUUACGGUUCACUGGCCCAAGGGGAUUUAUCACUCAUAAGUUCAGAGAAAGAUUAAUGAGAAAAAAGAAGGAAUAUACAGAUGUUGCCACAGGAAUCUAAUCUGAAAUCGUACAAAUGGAAAUGACGCUACAGGAGGAUGUUUGGGAGCAUCUCUCUCUUUUUGUCAGGAGUUAGAAGUGACACUAAGGCACUAAUACUGUAACUUCUUGAUAAAAUAACUUUAUUUUUUAGUAGUGGAAUGCUGCAACUUUUUUACACCUAACAAUUGCUUUUAAAUUACAGUAUUCAAUUUAAAAGUUGUAUUAACUACAGUUUCCUUUGCAAAAAGUCUCAAAAGAAUCACUUGAAGGGCAUUAUUUGUUGAUGCAUUUUUCUCUGAGCAUGGUUUCAUAGAGAGAACUUCACCAAGUAAUAUUCAGACGUUUAUAUGUUGAAAGUUUUGCUUACAUAAUAAAAACAAAAACAAGUGUCUGAAUUGUAUAGUGUCUUUACAUGAAAGAACUUUAAACAGUGGCCUUAUGGUAGAAAAUUUUAUACCAGAUUUUUCUUUUUCUGAUGACAUUUUGGCUUAUAACUCGAAGUUUUCUUAAGUUUCUGAAGAUCAAGGCCUAUAUAAUUCAUACAUUUCAUAUUAUAAGAAGGCAAGAGACAAGGUGCUUCAAAUAUUCCAUCAGGUAGUUGUGAGUGCACUGAAUUUUUAGUAAUAUGUUCAUUCAGUUUUUUUCCACAACUAUUUGCUCUUUUCCAAUUUCAAAAUGCUAUUGUGGAAAAUAUGUAAAGAUUUUGUAAUCUAUAGUCCAUCUUAUUUUUCCCUCAGGGCAAGCUUGUGCAUAUCAUAUUUUUAAAGGCUUUUUAAAAAUCUGACAAACAAAAUCUCAUAUUUGAAAAUUGUACUUUACUACUACAGCAUUACACAUUUUGCAAGCACAUCUUAUAGAGUGUUUACUUUUAGUUCAGUUGAUAUGUAUUGCAUACCUACUAUGUGUAAGAGCAAAUGGAUGGGAUUUUUAAAUGAAAUUUUUAGGCCCCAAUACCUUAUUUCUUUAUGUUUUCUGUGUUCUGCUUAACAGUACAUAUACAUUCCCAAUUACAUUUUUGUGAAAUGUUUAUUUGUAAUAAAAUAAAAUGUUGUUGCUCUUUCUGCUUAAAUAAGUUACUUGCCAGUUUGUGAGAGCAUUAUUUUAAUUUUGUUUGAGACUUAUAGCCUUGGAUAGCACCUCUGUUUAAACAGUGUUUAAAGCACUGUUCUGUGCUUACAAAGACAGAGCUUUCAAAAUUAAAAUGUGAAGGUUGAUAAGAACUUGGUUUUUCAUGACUGGAUGUGAAAAAUCUUAGUACAUUCAGUUUUCUUGUCCAUAUCUUUAAAAGAGAGGGCAGCCUUUUCCUUAAGUGAGUUCAUGAUAAGGGGGGCAAGUGCACUUGAUUCAUUGCUAAGCAGGUAAUAAAUUUGGGUAGAUGGCCUGUCUUGUACUGUGUACAAUCUCUAUAGGUCAGGUUUUCCAAACAUAUUUAGCAUUCCACUUAUGGUAAGAAAGAAAUGCAUGCACACAGGUAGUAUGGCAACUUUAUAUUGUGUUAGGUACUUAUAAAAUCUGUCUUAAAUUUUAAAAUAAUUGAUUUCAUUUACUCCCAUAUUCUAGGGGACAGUAAUGAGCUUUGAAUAUUUAAUCAUUUGAUUGACAACUAUGUAUUGCACAGAUACUGUACUAAAAUUACAGCAAUGAACAAGAAGACAAGACACAUGGACCCUGCCUUUAUGGUACGAAGAGUCUAAUAGGAAAAAUGGACAUUAAACAGAAAUAUAACUUGGUAAAUCGCCUUUAUAGCUCGCUUUUUAUUUAUUGUAACACAUAAAGGUAAGAUGGCUGAUUUACUAUUAUUCAUUCCACAACUGAUUCCCUAUUUGGAUAUUCUUUUGGCACUGUCUCAAUAUGCAAAGCGUGUUAUCUGCAAAAUACCUGUGCAGAAAACAUUGUGUGUAUAAGAUCUAAAGCCUAAAAGGAAAAACCAACUUUAUAAUUUAGAGUAUAAAAUAAGGACAGGGACCGUGUCUGUCUUGUCCACCAUAGUAUCCCCAGCACCCAGCUUCCUAUUUGACGUGUGGUAAGAGUUCAUUAAAUAUUAGUUGAAUAAUGAAUGAAUAAAUAGGGAAUAAUAGAAUAUGUUUAUUAGGAACUACAUGUGUAAUUUUCAUAUGGAGAUUGAACAAAAGGUUAUCCAUAGCAUUUUUUAUUGACUGGAAAGAAUUUGACUUCUUGAAUGCAUAAGACUUGAGAAGAGAAGUUUUUUUUUUUUUUCUUUUUUUUGAUAAGUCCCCUACCAUUGCCUCCUCACCUUCCUCCACUACGUGCUAGGCCCUUCGCUGGUACUGGGAAGACAAAGAUAAUAAGACACAGUCCCUGCUGUGAGGAAGCUCAUGCACUGCUGAAGAAGAGAUUCACAAAAACAAAGAAUCACAAUGUAGAGUAAGUACUUUAGUGGACAUAUAUACAAAAGGUUGAGAGGAAAGUUGACAUUUCUGAUUCAGCAUCCCCUCGUCAUGUUUCUUUCCUAUUGGUUUCACCAACCUCAGAAGGCACUAUUCUGUUGGUGGUUUUACUGGUUUUAAAAAUUGAUGCAUUGGGGGAAACUGGGUAAAUUGUACGCGGGAUCUCUCUGUAUUAUUUCUUUUAUAGCUGCAUGUGAAUCUAGAGUUACUUCAACAUAAAUUUCAAUUUGAAGAAUUGCCCAUAGUCUUAUCACAGAGAACACUAUUAUAAAUAUUUUAGAUGAUACAUUUUCAUUUUUUUCUAUUGGAAAAAAACUCGCUACAUUUAUGUGUAACAAUUUAUGUAGAUGUAUACUAUGUACCACAUUUUACCUAAUAAAUCCUACAUUUUUGAAUAGUUUUUUUUUUAAAAAAAAGACGGGGAUACUUCCAGGCAGAAGCAAGAAAAGUAAAGCUGGAUGAGAAACUCUUAUUGUCUUUAUUACCCAGCAAAUUCAGUAACCACCAGGCACAAAUUCACCAGGAACAACCAAGCAAGGAAGGAAGAAGAAGCUGAUGCAACAAGGUGUGGUAUGACUUCAUCCCUCGCCCAUCCCCAGAAGUAGCACUGAGUAAAACAAUGGAGAUGACAAAAAUAUUGGUAACAGUGGGCCCCAGUAUGGACAAAGGCACUGACGAGGUGACCAGGCCACGUGGAGGAGAGUCAAGGAAAACUCUUGGGACAACGAAGUCUUUGCUUCCAUCUCAGGACCUCAGCAGAAGGGGUAAGAUUCACCAGGACUAGGCAUUUCCCAGGUCUCAGAGCAGCCUGGGAAAGCCAAAUCCUGCAGAAGUCAGAGACACCUUUGACUGUGUCUAGUGAGUUCUGGUUCUGGACAUUUAAUGGGAACCUAGAAGAGAGGGGAUACCAGGUUCCCCAACAAAGUUCCGUCAAAUAGGAUGAUUAUGAGCUCUGAGUCCAUUAAAAUACAGAAUGAACAUUUAAGAACUGAGGAAUCAUAGAUGUAGAAUAGUAUGUAAAUGUUAUAAAUCUUGACAAAGAAAAAUUAAUGUACAUUGACAAAUUCAGACAUGGAGGAGGUAAAGUGGGAUAAAGACUUAAGAACUAACCGUCUCAUCAUUCAUGGCCAGGUGUCAUGUCACGUCAUGUCUUAAAAUUAUAAUAUGGGGAAAAACGCUAGUGACCAACCUUAAGUUUUUCCACAAUCUUUUUUUUCCUUGACCUUAAUACAGUGGUUCUCAAAGUGUGGUCCCAGACCAGCAACAUCAGCAUCACCUGAGAACUUGUUAAAAAUGCAGAUUCUUGGCCCCACCCCAGACCUCCUGAAUCAGAAACCCUGGGGGUGGGGCCAAGCAAUCUGUGAUUUAACAAGUCCUCCAGGGGAUUCUGGCACAUACUUGAGUUUGAGAAUAACUGGCUUAUUUAUCCCUUUUAGGAACCAAUGAAGAAACAUUUAUCUGAAGUUCAGCAGCCCCUUCAAUUUAAUGCCUAAUUUUUUUUCUAUUGCAUUCAAAUAAAGUUAAAUCUAAAACUUGUUUGCUGGCCGGGCACAGUGAGUCACGCCUGUAAUCCCAGCACUUUGGGAGGCCGAGGCGAGUGGAUCACUUGAGGUCAGGAGUUUGAGACCAGCCUGGCCAAUAUGGUGAAACCCCAUCUCUAAUAAAAAUACAUAAAUUAGCCGGGCGCAGUAGCAUGCACCUGUAAUCCCAGCUACCUGGGAGGCUGAGGCAGGAGAAUUGCUUAAACCCGGGAGGCGAAGGUUGCAGUGAACCGAGGCCACGCCAUUGCACUCCAGCCUGGGCGACAGAGCGAGACUCCAUGUCAAAAAAGAAAAUAAAUAAAUAAAACUUGUUAGAAUAAAAAGUUUAGGGAUUCCCCCCGUCAAUCCUGUCUGUACAUAUGAGUGAAUUGAGAGGUCUGGAAACAUACCCACCCACUGUUAACACUGUUGAUUUUUUUAAAUGGUGGGAUUAUGAGUGACUGUACUCUUCUGUAUCUAUCAAAUAUAAUGAAUGUUGUAUCAUUUUUAUAAAAUAAAGUCUUUCUUUUUUAAAA